ACCUAGAGAGCGGCGCGUGCGCAGCGGGAGUCGAAGCGGAGAUCCCGGGGUCGCGCGAGAGCCGCAAGCGGAGUUGGUGGGCGCUAUGCUAUCACCCGAGGCAGAGCGAGUGCUGCGGUACCUUGUAGAAGUGGAGGAGCUCGCCGAGGAGGUGCUGGCGGACAAGCGGCAGAUUGUGGACCUGGACACUAAAAGGAAUCAGAAUCGAGAGGGCCUGAGGGCCCUGCAGAAGGAUCUCAGCCUCUCUGAAGAUGUGAUGGUUUGCUUCGGGAACAUGUUUAUCAAGAUGCCUCACCCUGAGACAAAGGAAAUGAUUGAAAAAGAUCAAGAUCAUCUGGAUAAAGAAAUAGAAAAACUGCGGAAGCAACUUAAAGUGAAGGUCAACCGCCUUUUUGAGGCCCAAGGCAAACCGGAGCUGAAGGGUUUUAACUUGAACCCCCUCAACCAGGAUGAGCUUAAAGCUCUCAAGGUCAUCUUGAAAGGAUGAGACUCAAGAACCAAGAUGGGGGACCAGCAACCCCCCAGGGUCAUGGAGGACCCAGGACCCUCCAACCUUGACACCUGUAAGGACAGGAUCUGCCCUGUAAGGGGCCAGCCGUCAGGAAUCUGGCCAUGAAAACCUCUUUGUAGUGCUUGGCUACUCUGUGAUGGCAGGAGGGAACCUUCAGCCUGUCUGGCUGCUGGACCUGGACACCAGGGCUCGGUGGACACAAGAUCUAUUGACGGGCCUUGGUAGCCACCAGUGGGUGUGUGGGGCAGUGGCUGUGGGGGUGUAAGAAUGACUGCAACAGGCACUUCCCAACAAUGGCCUGCUGUUCACAUGGACCCUGAGCAAGGAAGGAGGGAGGGAGGGGCAGAGUGGAGUGUCAUUCCAGCAUUCCUCUCAGAAGGGAGAGAGGUUUUCAGGCUGGUGCCAUGCGAUUGGAAUAAAGCAGGAGGCUCAUGGGUGGUUGCUGAAUGAAGAACAGAAUCUUGGUGCUUUGUGGCUCACCACAGCCAUCUGUGGGGCAGGCACACACACCUCCCGCCAGCUCCAAUUUUGCACUUUUUCCCUGCUUGAUUCCAAGAGUAGGUGCUGCCUAGCAGCCCUUCGUGGCCACUCUUUACUCAGGAGGGCCUUGCAGAGUCCUGCACCAGGCCUGGGUGAGUGGAUGCGCCUCUUACCAUAUGACACGUGUCAAGAUGCCCUUCCGCCCCCUCUGAAAGUGGGGCCCGGCCAGCACUGCUCGUUACUGUCUGCCUUCAGUGGUCUGAGGUCCCAGUAUGAACUGCCGUGAAGUCAAAACUCUUAUGUGUUCAUUAAGGGCUCAAUAAAUGUUAGCUGAAUGAAUGAAUAGCAGCAACUAGUCUUUAUUUGCCUCAUCUAGUCCUUCAGUAAGGGCACGCCACUCCAUUUAGAAUACAACCUAUGAACAUGGUUCUUGCCUUGAAAUAAACCUGUGAUUUGACAGGCGGGUGAUAACAAAUGGCAGCAUGGCAGGGGCACACCUCUCCUGGUCCCCCCGCUCCUUGGCUCUGGCUCAUAGUUACAUAGAAACACAGGCUGUCAUGGCCAGUUCUUACGUGUUUUCAAGAGAAGCUAGACAUAUGGGUUGUGAAGUUGAAUCUCCUUUUAAAUAUUUUUGACUAAUGCAGAAACUUUUAAAACAUGAGUGUGGGUCACAGGUGUUAGCUCCAGAUAGUGCAAUACCAUACAACUAUAAUCAAGAAUAAGGAACAAGCUCCAAGAUACAUCAAGUGAGGAAAGCAAGGGGAAGGCUGGUGUCUUAUAAGCUAAUAAUUUUUGUGCAAGCACAGUGUGAUUCCCUCAGAACAGCACCUGCAGGGUUGGGGCGCACAGGUGGGAGGGAAGGAGAUGUCACCCUAUACCCUUUUGUAAACUUUGGAUUUUAAACCGUAUGAAUAUAUUGCUUAUUUUAAAAUGUAAAUAAAGUAGGGAGUUGCAGAAUUCACCUUG